GUUUUUGUUGUUGGUGAAAGGUGAGGGGAACAGCUGAUCCGUCUGUUGGGUAAGAAACUUGGCCUAAUUGGGGGCGAUCUUAUGGGAGGGGAGGGUCACCCCACUUUCCAGUUUGGGGAAGGAUAACGUAAGGGAACUGUCGAAGGGGAAUACAGGAGCGUUUGGGUUGUAACCCUUUCCGUACUGGAGAAGCCACCCCCGCUGUUUGGGGAGUUCUUGGUUUCAAGGGGACUCUGAUUGGGGGUGGGGGGCGCCCCCUCGUCGUCCUCUCCUUCUUCUCAAUGCGUCUCUAUAAAGCUGAUCCCUUCAAGGGAGCUGAAAUCUGCUUAUUCGCUCCCAGGCAAGACGUGUCCCCUACACGUCUUCCCUCUCUCCCCUACGCAAAUCCAAAGGCCUUUACGACGCUGAAUCCCUGGGGAGGAAGGGGGACCUUCCAAGGUGUAGAAUGUCAAGGAACUCUAGAGCCCUACAGAGUAGGGGAUGGGACACCCGCUCUCCGCCCCAUCAUGUGAACAUCUGAAUCAGGCUACACACCUACAUCUUAGGUGCCCAAAACUUUCUUUCGGACAUGAAGAACGUUUACAGCUGUUACGGAUUUUCUUUGUGGGGUGUAUUUUAGGGUUCUCCAGGUAUAUCUUUGGGGACAAUUUACCCCCACCCUUAGAAAGCUGGAAGAAUUGCAUUUGGAGAAAACAUGGAUUAGUUUCAACCAGGAAUUUUUCAGGGAGAUGAACAUUAAAAAAAACUUUUUGUUCUACCUAUUUGGGGGACAGAAGUUGCUCCUUUUUGUGUUGCUGGCUCACCUUUAUCCACUGAGUUUCUGUUUUCUUUUAAAGUUCCUGUCCCCUGGACUUCAGCCUGGUGUGGGUUUGUGAUGUUUGGGGGCGUGCAUAUGACUAGUGACAAUGGCUGGUUGGACAUGUCAGCUGUGAGUGACACAGGAAAUAGAUUAGUGGGCUGGAAAGGAGUGAUGAAUAAGAGGGCCAUCUCACAGCCCUGGACUGAGGAGUUCUUUUGAUCGUUAUUAUUGUUAUCUGUCCUCACCCCACCCUCAUAUUUUCCAAUUAACUCUCCCCAGCUAACUUGGAACACCCCUUCCUCUCAACCCCAUCCUGUAGUGUGUCUCCAGCUACCAAUACAAACAGAUGGAAGGAUGGAGGCUGAGGGGAGCAGAGAGAAAAUGAGGAGAGAAAUACUAAAGUGAAACCAGUAGGUUUCUAGUCCUGCUGCAGGCACAGUCUGGAGAGAAGAAUAGAUUAGUUGCUGCUUUCUGAUGUCAUAACUCAUUCCUGGAUACAGCUGGGUCAACAAGCUUAGGAGUAGGAGGACAGAUAUCUCAAGGCCAGGAUGGAAGAAUCACCACUAAGCCGGGCACCAUCCCGUGGUGGAGUCAACUUUCUCAAUGUAGCCCGGACCUACAUCCCCAACACCAAGGUGGAAUGUCACUACACCCUUCCCCCAGGCACCAUGCCCAGUGCCAGUGACUGGAUUGGCAUCUUCAAGGUGGAGGCUGCCUGUGUUCGGGAUUACCACACAUUUGUGUGGUCUUCCGUGCCUGAAAGUACAACUGAUGGUUCCCCCAUUCACACCAGUGUCCAGUUCCAAGCCAGCUACCUGCCCAAACCAGGAGCUCAGCUCUACCAGUUCCGAUAUGUGAACCGCCAGGGCCAGGUGUGUGGGCAGAGCCCCCCUUUCCAGUUCCGAGAGCCAAGGCCCAUGGAUGAACUGGUGACCCUGGAGGAGGCUGAUGGGGGCUCUGACAUCCUGCUGGUUGUCCCCAAGGCAACUGUGUUACAGAACCAGCUCGAUGAGAGCCAGCAAGAACGGAAUGACCUGAUGCAGCUGAAGCUACAGCUGGAGGGACAGGUGACAGAGCUGAGGAGCCGAGUGCAGGAGCUCGAGAGGGCUCUGGCAACUGCCAGGCAGGAGCACACGGAGCUGAUGGAACAGUACAAGGGGAUUUCCCGGUCCCAUGGGGAGAUCACAGAAGAGAGGGACAUCCUGAGCCGGCAACAGGGAGACCAUGUGGCACGCAUCCUGGAGCUAGAGGAUGACAUCCAGACCAUCAGUGAGAAAGUGCUGACGAAGGAAGUGGAGCUGGACAGGCUUAGAGACACAGUGAAGGCCCUGACUCGGGAACAAGAGAAGCUCCUUGGGCAACUGAAAGAAGUACAAGCAGACAAGGAGCAAAGUGAGGCUGAGCUCCAAGUGGCACAACAGGAGAACCAUCACUUAAAUUUGGACCUGAAGGAGGCGAAGAGCUGGCAAGAGGAGCAGAGUGCUCAGGCUCAGCGACUGAAAGACAAGGUGGCCCAGAUGAAGGACACCCUAGGCCAGGCCCAGCAGCGGGUGGCCGAGCUGGAGCCCUUGAAGGAGCAGCUUCGAGGGGCCCAGGAGCUUGCAGCCUCAAGCCAGCAGAAAGCCACCCUUCUUGGGGAGGAGUUGGCCAGUGCAGCAGCAGCCAGGGACCGCACCAUAGCCGAACUACACCGCAGCCGCCUGGAAGUGGCUGAAGUUAACGGCAGGCUGGCUGAGCUCGGUUUGCACUUGAAGGAAGAAAAAUGCCAAUGGAGCAAGGAGCGGGCAGGGCUGCUGCAGAGUGUGGAGGCAGAGAAGGACAAGAUCCUGAAGCUGAGUGCAGAGAUACUUCGAUUGGAGAAGGCAGUUCAGGAGGAGAGGACCCAAAACCAAGUGUUCAAGACUGAGCUGGCCCGGGAGAAGGAUUCUAGCCUGGUACAGUUGUCAGAAAGUAAGCGGGAGCUGACAGAGCUGCGGUCAGCCCUGCGUGUGCUCCAGAAGGAAAAGGAGCAGUUACAGGAGGAGAAACAGGAAUUGCUAGAGUACAUGAGAAAGCUAGAGGCCCGCCUGGAGAAGGUGGCAGAUGAGAAGUGGAAUGAGGAUGCCACCACAGAGGAUGAGGAGGCCGCUGUGGGGCUGAGCUGCCCGGCAGCUCUGACAGACUCAGAGGACGAGUCCCCAGAAGACAUGAGGCUCCCACCCUAUGGCCUUUGUGAGCGUGGAGACCCAGGCUCCUCUCCUGCUGGGCCUCGAGAGGCUUCUCCCCUUGUUGUCAUCAGCCAGCCGGCUCCCAUUUCUCCUCACCUCUCUGGGCCAGCUGAGGACAGUAGCUCUGACUCGGAGGCUGAAGAUGAGAAGUCAGUCCUGAUGGCAGCUGUGCAGAGUGGGGGUGAGGAGGCCAACUUACUGCUUCCUGAACUGGGCAGUGCCUUCUAUGACAUGGCCAGCACCAUCUUCUGCAGAGCCCAAAUUGCCCUGCUUCCCCUCUCUCCUGCCUCUACCCCUUCCCCAACCACCAGUGGCUUUACAGUGGGUACCCUGUCAGAAACCAGCACUGGGGGCCCUGCCACCCCCACAUGGAAGGAGUGUCCUAUCUGUAAGGAGCGCUUUCCUGCUGAGAGUGACAAGGAUGCCCUGGAGGACCACAUGGAUGGACACUUCUUUUUCAGCACCCAGGACCCCUUCACCUUUGAGUGAUCUUACUCCCUCGUACAUGCACAAAUACACACUCAUGCACACACACACUCACACACAUGCAUACACUUAGGUUUCAUGCCCAUUUUCUAUCACACUGGGCUCCAUGAUAUUCUGUUCCCUAAGAACUGCUUCUGUGUGCCCUGUUUUCAUCCCAAGAUUUCUCACUUCAUCCUCUCCUACCUGGCUCUUUUGUCCCAGGGAGGGGUCCUGUUCGGAAGCAGUGGCUGAAUUUAUCCCCUGAAAGUGGUUUUGGAGGAACCGGGAUGGAGGAGGCCUUCCCCUGUGGGAAUAGAAUCGUCCACUCCUAGCCCUGGUUGCUUCUGAUACACAGCCACUGCACACACACACUCACACUCACACUCCCUUGUCUGAUGCCCCAAAGCCAAUUCCUGGGGCACCCUACCCUCUCUUAUUUGGAGUUUCCGUUGGUUUACCUGAGUUUUCUCUGGGGUCUGCACAGAGGCAGCAGCAUGGACAUCAUGGCCUCUCAGGUCCCUUUUGGUUCUCAGUUUCAUUGGUUCCUCUUUCUGUUCCCCCAUUGACUUCUGUGCCCCACCCUAGCCUUUUCCAUAACCUUAGGUAUUCAGUUUGGAGGGGUUUUUUGUAUUUUUGAGGAUUCCUGUAUUCUGUAUCCUCUCCUCGCAUCUCCUCACAUGGAAAGAAAUAAUGUAUUUGUGCCUUCUGUGAGGAAUGGGGGGAACAAGUGGUCCCAGGUAUCCCCAUUUCCAAGGCCCCCCUCCCUCUCCAGGUCCCCCCACAGCAAUAAAAGCUUCCCCCUGAUAUCCAUCCCUUUGUAGUUUGAACAAAUAUAUUUAUAUGAUAUGUAUGACUGUUGUCACAAAAUGUGUUCUUAUCAUGAGGUGUGACUGGAACACAGGGCCCAGACCUCCAGCUCUUAGACCCUGGUGGAGGGAGGAGGGAAAGAGGGGACGCAUCCCUGCCUCAUGGCAGGGGAUGCUGGGCAGUUACUGUCCUGUCGUGCCUCCUGGUGUGCUGGCCAUGAGUGGGUUGUCUCAAGUGGGAGUCUGGCUUGGAUAAUGCGGCAGUUGGGGAGGGAGCAAACUCAUGGGUCCCUGUCACUUCUGCUCAGGGUUUAGUCCCAGGGUGGGUGCAUGCCAUGGAAAAGUGGGACAAGUUUCCCACUGCCGAGAACUUCACCCUUCAUAGCAGCCAUCACUGUACCUUAUGCCAAAGGACAGGCUUUAUUCCUGUCAAGAGCGUACACCUUUGAGUAUCUACUUAGUAAAAAAUGCCCUAAGCCUCAUACCUCUAAAGGCGAUUUUAUAUUCCUCCUGUUUCUGUUUCUGUUUCUUUCUCUGUUGCCAUCCCCUCAUACCUGUAUGCACACUCUGCCUCAACAGUCACAAAAACACAUUCAUCCACUCUAACCAGCUUCACAGGCUAGACAGACACAUACACAGCAUCGUAAAGCAUUUGUUAAGGACCUGCACGCUCACCAAGGCUCUCAGCAAUGGCCUGCACAAGCACAUGCCUACAACCCCCUCGUCCUCCAACCCAAUAGCUCCCUUCUCAGCUGCCCUCCUCUCCCUUCAGGGCCCCUGUGUGGACCACCCCCACCAUUCCCUUUCUCCAUUCACCUGAAAUGCUCCUGUCCACCCCCUUUCCAGCCCCACCUGGAUGACUUCUUACAUCGUUCCUUCUUCCCUCACGUCUCCGUCUCCUAGCAACCCCAUCCCGUUCCCUGAAUCCCUUCCAAGGAAAUUAGAGAUAAUGGAUCUCUCCUCUCUCCAUCCCAACCCCUCUUUAUUGAUCCUCCUUUAAUGAAAGUUAAUUAUAACAAUGAUUUAAUUAAUAGAAUCCCUCUCUUCCUUUAUUGCUUCCCGUAUUAAGACUAUUAAUAAAUACGAGCUGGGCUGACAGAGGCAUCCAUCACCCGCCUGGGAUUCCCCCCAUCCCUCCUUUUACCUUCCCCCCUCUCCCUCUCCCUCUCUUGGCCUAUAAACUUGCCGGGGUAGUGGGGGUUAAUCAGAGAGGAAUUAUGAGCCAACAUCCCCAGCAGGAGGUGCAUUUAAUGAAAUCAUGUGUGAUUUAUUUUCUGGGGGAGGUUGGGGCGAGAAGAAUCUGGGACCCACACCUCCUGGCUUCCAGUGAGUGGCUGCCUUGUGCAAAAAAGGAGAAUAGUAGACAAACAGGAACCCAGGCCCCUGCUCCCAUGCCACAGCCCCUGCCAAGCCGCACAUACACCCACAGGAGCCACAUGGCUAGCUGCACAAGGCCACUGAUACAGACACUGUCAGACUAAAAGCACUUAAGAGGACUGCGGUAUAGGUUUUGUUCUUUCCAACCUCGAAAACUUCACAUGGGUCCUUCUCACCUCCUUCCUUUCUCUCCAGCCCUGUUCUGCUUCACUGUCCCGAAUCUGCUUCAUACUCCCCUCCUCCAUGAAGCCCCCCAACCCCCCACCAGGCUCCUCAACAUGGAUAUCUAGAGUUUCUAGCUGCUCCUUUCUCUGCCCUUUGUGUGUCUUUCUGGCAUGCAAUUUGCAGUUUCAGACUGGGGGUGCCACAAAAUGUGGGGCCAUUUCUCUUCCUUACUCAUGGUUUGCCUAUCCCAGUAUCCAAAGCAUGGUCCCCGACACAGAGGGGGCUCAAGGAAGGGUAAUUGACGGCAUGGGCUGGGGGAAACCCAGGGGCAGCCAGCUUCCAAUUCUAGUUCUCUUUCCUACUCACUGAGGGGUAUUUGGCAACUCAGCCUUUCUACUUAUUUCUCUUCUAUAAUGGAUCAUCCCUUUCCUCCCUGCUCCCCAGCAUCCAUGCAAAAGCCGAUAGAUCUGAAUGGGCUUGAGACUCUAAUGUGAAAGGAGAUGUCAGCCAAGUAGCAGCAAAUAGGAACUCGCGUCAGUAUUUGGUGGUGAAAGAACGAAUCCAAACACACCACUCCCCCACUUAUCGAACCUCAAUGGCCACCUGUUACCUACAGGAAUGAGAAAUGUAGAUUGCUUAGUGUGCCAGUCAGGGUCUUCACCAUCUGUCCCAACUUGCCCUUCCAUUUCCCAUCUACCCUAAGGAACCCUGUACUCCAGUAUAACAGAACCAUUCCACAAAAACAUACACUACUUUCCUCCUAGCUCAAAGGAUACCACCUACAUGGAGCCUUACUUGACUGCCCUCAGUUAUCCUUUGACAUACCACGUAGAGCACUUUAUAAAAAGAUGCUACAUGUGUUUACAACUUUUUAUUCUCCCUAAACUGUAAGCAACUUGAAGGCAGAUUCUAUGCUUAUACAUCACUGUGUUCCUAAAAUCUAGUAUAGAGACUGGAACAUAGGACCAGUCCUCCAGAAAUAAUCUUUAAGUUAUUUUAAUGAAAUGUUUUAUACAUACAAAAUAAUAUAUGUAAUGAAUAAUAAAGUGAACAUCAUUGAGCUCACCAACUAGCUUCAAAUAAAUAUUACCAAUACCAUUAAA